UGUAACUAACCUGCACAUUGUGCACAUGUACCCUAAAAUUUAAAGUAUAAUAAAAAAAUAAGUGUUGUCUGGGAUGUGGAAAACUUGGAACCCUCAUACAUUGCUGGUGGGAACAUAAAUUGGUGCUGGCACCUUAAAAUGUCAAACAUAGUUAUGACCCAGCAAUUCCAUACCUAUGUAUAUACCCAAGAGAAAUGAAAACAUAUGUCCACGCAAAAACUUAUGCAUGGAUGUUCAUAGCAGCAUUAUUCAUAAUAUCCCACAAGUGGGAUAUUAUUAGCUAUAUUUAGUUAUAAAAUAGCCCAAAGUGGAAAUAACCCAAAUAUUUAUAAAUUGAUGAAUGGAUAAAUAUAAAAUAUGUUCUAGGCAAGGUGCGGUGGCUCAUGCCUGUAAUGCCAACAUUUUGGAGGCUGAAGUGGGAGGAUUGCUUGAGGCCAGGAGCUCGAGACCAGCCUGGGCAAUAUAGGGAGACCCCAUAUCUACAAAAAAUUAAAAAAUUAGCUUGGUGUGAUGGCAUGCACCUGUAAUCCCAGCUACUCGGGAAGCUGAGGUGGGAUGAUCACUUGAGCCCUGGAGGUGGAGGCUGUAGUAAGUGGUUGCACCACUGCACUCCAGCUGGGUGACAGAGUGAGACCCUGUCUCAAAAAAAAAAAAAAAUGUUUUCUAUCUACACAAUGGAAUACUAUGUGGCAAUAAAAAGGGAAUGAAAUACUGAUACAUGCUACAACAUAGAUGAACCUUGAAAACAUCAUACUAAAUGAAAGAAGCCAGUCACAAAGACCACAUAUUUUAUAAUUCCAUUGAUAGGAAAUGUUUAGGAUAGACAAAUCUAUAGAGUCAGAAAGUAGAUUAGUGGUUGCUGGAGCUGGGAAGAGGAUGGGAAUGGAGAGUGACUGCUAAUGGGACUGGGUUUCUUUUUGAGGUGGCAAAAAUGUUCUAACUUAGGUUAUGCUAAUUGUUCCACUAUUCUGUGAAUACAAUAAAAUGCACUGAACUGUGUACUUUAAAGGGUGACAUAUGUGAAUUACAUCUCAAUAAAGCUGUUUUUUAAAAAAAAAAGGUCACAGAGCCCUGAACAGUGUGGUAGAAGUGAGGGGAGAUGGACAUGGCGGAAGGCCCUGGACACACAUCUUUAUCCCUUUGUGUGGCUACUUGCAGUUCCCGCCAAACCGGACCCAUCUCUUUGUCCCCAGAGGCGAAGUCCAGUGGACCUUGGUUUUUCACUUCAAGACCAGUUUUGGGGUCAAGGCUAUUUCAACAUGGCAGACAGUAAGAGUUAAAUAAAUGCUUGGUGAAUGAACCUACAUUGCAUCAAUGUACAGGCCACCAGAAGUACUUAAGGCUGGAGCAGUCUCCAGGGCUGGGGAGGGGAUCUCAGCAGGUUUUUAAAGGAAGGGACAGAACUUAAGAGCUCCUAAAAUGUUCCUUCAGAAGAACCCUGAGUCUAGAGGAGAGUUAACUCAUACCUAACGUGCAGUGAGAAAAGUCUCACAUUUUUUCUUUAAAUUCUUGUGCUGUAUGCAUCCUACUCUAUUAUUUCCAGCUUGUUUUAAUUUAAAAAUACUGUAAAUUGCCAUUCAGUAAAACGGAUGCCUCAGGGAGUUGUGCUGUUUAUUCUUGCAUCCUGGAAUACCUGUGGGUGUAUGCUGCUAUGUUCCCUCAGAGGAGCCCAGUCAACAAAUACCCAGAGUGCCCGCUGUGUGCUUGGCACAAGGGGUGCUGUUGCCAACACAGGAUCUGCCCUCAUGGGACUUUCAGUUGAGAAAUAAGUGCAUAGCCCUGAGGAGCAGAAAGAGCUUGGUGGAGAGGACAGAAUUAUGGGGGGCAGAGUUUGGAAGCUCGUAAGAACAUUGCCUUAAAUGAAGACCAACAUUUAUGCUCAGUGUUUUACUAGGAAAAAGUUGAAAACUGCCUAAAUGUCUACCAGUGGAAUGGCUAAAAAAAUUAUGGUGUUACCAUAUAGUAGGAUAUUAUGUAGCUAUUUAAUAAUAAAAAACAAUAAAGGAAAAGGCUUAUGAUGAAAUUUUAUGUAAAAAAUCUUGAAAAAAAACUAUACAUAGUAUGGUCUCAACAUGUAAAACAUACUCAGAAAAAAUACCAGCAUAGAAUGCCCCAAAUGCUAGUUGACUUUGGAGGGUAGAAUUAUGGGGGGAUUUCUCUCUCUCUCCCCAAAUUUUCUACAGUAAGUCUGGGUUAUGUUAUUAAUAAACAUCACAUCUUUGAUGCGGGAAGGCUAAUCUACAGCUGCAUGUGGGGGCAGGGCUAGAGAUGAACCUGGAGUAGGGGCCACAGAGUAGACCGGGGAGGAAGGGCUAGAGAUGGAGAUGUGGGUGCCGUCUUCCUACAGGAGAGGUCAAAACAAACCCUGAGUGGGCACUGAGGGAGCCCGUGAAGAAACCGCAGAGAGCUGAGGAGUCUCGCGGGGCAGGAGGAGGAAUUGGAGUCAGGGAUGAGGAGAGUCAAGUGUCAUGGAGCUGGGCAGAGAUUCUAGGCAGAGUAGUAUCUAGAAAUCCUUGGAAGUCAAGGAGAGAGGUUGAAAGAGGAGCCCUCAGUGUAAAACCUUGUCUCCUUCCUAGAGUGGUGAGGUUAGAUUUCAAUGAGAUAUAGGAGAGUGAUUAGCUAUACAGGCUCUGGAGUUGGGCAGACCAGUUCAAACCUCAGUUUCAGAACUUACAGCUAAGUGACCUUGGAAAAACUAUCUAACCUCUCUGAACCUGUUUCCCCAUCUGUUAAAUGGAACCAAUAAAAACCAUUAGGUUAUUUUUUGGAUUAGAUGAAUAAUGCAUGGAAAGUGUUUUGCACAGUGCUUGGCACAUAUAUGUACUAUUUUUUUUAAGAGACAGAACCUUACUUAAUCACCCAUAGCUCAUGUAACCUCAAACUCCUGGACUCAAGUGAUCCUCUAUCACUUCAGCCCCCACUAUGCCUAACUAAAAAAAAAAAAUUUCUAAAGAUAGGGUCUUGCUAUGCUGCUCAGGCUGACUGUGUACUAAUUGGAUGAUGUCUAUUAUUAUUGGUUUACUACAGUUGUUAAUAUUAUGCAAAAUAUCUUUGAUCUAUAAAGAGCUUCUCCUGGUCCUUUGGGCAGGGCUUUCUCAGGGUAAGACGACCUCUGGAUGCUCACCCUGCCCUCUUCACCUCUCGUCCCCAGCUGUUUCCUCUGCCACCAUGAGGAACAUUUUCAAGAGGAACCAGGAGCCUAUUGUGGCUCCUGCCACCACCACCGCCACGAUGCCCAUUGGACCCGUGGACAACUCCACUGAGAGUGGGGGUGCUGGGGAGAGCCAGGAGGACAUGUUUGCCAAACUGAAGGAGAAGUUAUUCAAUGAGAUAAACAAGAUUCCCUUACCACCCUGGGCACUGAUCGCCAUUGCUGUGGUUGCUGGGCUCCUGCUUCUCACCUGCUGCUUCUGCAUCUGCAAGAAAUGCUGCUGCAAGAAGAAGAAGAACAAGAAGGAGAAGGGCAAAGGCAUGAAGAAUGCCAUGAACAUGAAGGACAUGAAAGGGGGUCAGCUCCCACAGGAUGACGACGACGCAGAGACAGGCCUGACUGAGGGGGAAGGUGAAGGGGAGGAGGAGAAAGAGCCAGAGAACCUGGGCAAACUGCAGUUUUCCCUGGACUAUGAUUUUCAGGCUAAUCAGCUUACUGUGGGCGUUCUGCAGGCUGCUGAACUGCCUGCCCUGGACAUGGGAGGCACCUCAGACCCUUAUGUCAAGGUCUUCCUCCUUCCUGACAAGAAGAAGAAAUAUGAGACCAAAGUCCAUCGGAAGACACUGAACCCUGCCUUCAAUGAAACCUUCACCUUCAAGGUGCCAUACCAGGAGCUUGGGGGCAAAACUCUGGUGAUGGCCAUCUAUGACUUUGACCGCUUCUCCAAACAUGACAUCAUUGGAGAGGUAAAGGUGCCUAUGAACACAGUGGACCUCGGCCAGCCCAUUGAGGAGUGGAGAGACCUGCAAGGCGGGGAAAAGGAGGAGCCGGAGAAGCUGGGCGACAUCUGCACCUCCCUGCGCUAUGUGCCCACGGCCGGGAAGCUCACUGUCUGCAUCCUGGAGGCUAAGAACCUCAAGAAGAUGGACGUGGGCGGCCUUUCAGACCCGUACGUGAAGAUCCACCUGAUGCAGAAUGGCAAGAGGCUCAAGAAGAAGAAGACAACCGUGAAGAAGAAGACCCUGAACCCAUACUUCAACGAGUCCUUCAGCUUUGAGAUCCCCUUCGAGCAGAUUCAGAAAGUCCAGGUAGUGGUCACCGUGCUGGACUAUGACAAGCUGGGCAAGAACGAAGCCAUAGGCAAGAUCUUCGUGGGCAGCAAUGCCACGGGCACAGAGCUGCGGCACUGGUCCGACAUGCUGGCCAACCCCCGGAGGCCCAUCGCCCAGUGGCACUCGCUCAAGCCUGAGGAGGAGGUGGAUGCACUCCUGGGCAAGAACAAGUAGACAGCAGCGGCUGGGACCCCACACCUUUCACGGACACUGACAAGAUCCAGAGCUAUCAAUACCUCAGUUAUGCAACCUUAGAGGUUUUCUUUUUUCUUUCAUUUGUUGGGUGGUUGUGUCCUUGUUUUUCCUUGUUUUUCUCUUUUUAAAGACCAACUUCCCUUUGAUGGCUGUGUGAGGAGAGUCCCCUAAGAGGUGAAAGAGAAGCCUGGCUCUGUUCACGGUCCCAGGAGCUGUCCUUGCUGCAUGCCCUGUCACAGUUCCCUCGACUCUUUCAAAGCUUCACAUCUGCCUCACCCCAAGCGAGGCUCUCUACUGGCACAAACUUGCAGCAGUUCCUGUUUUUUGAGCCUUCUGGACCAACAAAAUGGCAGCACAUCCUGCUUCCUGACAGGGAAGGCAUCACAGUGGCCAAUGAUCGUGUGUGUGUGUGUGUGUGUGUGUGUGUAUGUGUGUGUGUGUGUGUGUGUGUGUGUGUGUGUGUGUGUCUUUGAGCAUUUCUCUUCAUUCCUGGAAUGUGUGUGUGUGUGUGUCUCUUUGAGCAUCUCUCUUCAUUCCUGGAAUGAGCCAUGGACAGUAAAGUUGUGUGGGAAAAGAAGGCUCUUUGGGGACCCUGACAUGAAGAAGUCCACUAAGUGGGAGAUCUUCUCUCAUCUAUGGCAAAGUCUCAGGAUCCUGUUCAGAUAUCGGGGCUUUCAUACUCCUGUUGGUGGCUAUUUGGGAGGCAGCAAGAUGUGAAGACUGGAUGUGUUCAGAACUAGGACCAAACGAUGCCAUCAAAUACUUCCUCCUGCCAGUCAUGGUUUCCCCAGAAGUGUAGUUCCUGGGACAUUCAUGGAUAUGAGCUAUUCACUAGUUGGGUCAGACUAACAGGGACUCUCAGUCCCAAAAUCUCACUCUUAUUGACAAUAAAUAUCAAACUAUGAAGAAACAGAAGUCCCAUUACCAGAAAGACCAAAAUUAAACUCCUGGAUCUUCACCCCAUCCAGUGGGAAACACAGAUGCUUUCUCCCUUUCCAGAAUAUAAGCAGCCAAGUUCAUUUGCAUUUAUUCCCCAUUGUGCUUUUGCUUCUGUUUCUCUUUUAAGUGGAGCAACACUGUCUGAAGACACGUUAUCUGUGCAGAGCCAGAGAACUUUAAAAGGAAAGUUUAAAUGUUCUUAGUUCUCCUGAGGUCCAGGUAAGAAGGGGGUGGUAAGAAGAGGAUGGGGGACAGAUGGCUGAGAUCCCUUGGGAGGAGAUAUAGGGGAGCACUGGAAUUCCCCCGACUCCCACUCCUUGCUCCCUUGGCCCUCUGCCCUCCAUGCUGGAGAGCUGAUAGGUAGCUGGAGUGGCCCAGGGAGACCUAUGGGAAGGACCCGUCCUACCAUUAGGGGGCUUCUCUCUAUGAAUGCUAAGAAACAAAGGGCAUCCAUUCCAAAUGAGUAGCAGAGGUGACCUUCUAGGGUUUCUACCCAUGCUCAGUUGUAUCCCAUUCCCUGUUCACCUUUUGUCCCCAGCACUGAUAUAAAAGCCAUAUAUAUGUUAGUCAGGUUUGCACUGAGUCUUCUUCCAAUCCUUCAGCCUGGACAACAGAGUGAGGUCCCCUUGUGGCCAGAGGCCAGCCCUCCUUGCCUGCCUUCCUUUGACCUCUCUUUUCCAUCCAUGAAGCCCUCAGGCCCUUGCCAUUUUUUCACCACAGAAAACUCAUGGCUUCUCCAGAAGCCUGAGUAUCUCUCUUUCCCAGCACAAAUGGCAGCAUCUCUAUCCUGCCCCAUCUGGGCCACUUCAGCUUCCUGUAGACACCCAAGACAGAUGGACAGUGUUGGAGGGAAUCAGGCUUUGAGGAUCCAGUGUGAAGAAGUUGCAGAGUGUCUUUUUAUUUUAUUUUAAAAAGGGGGAAGGGGCUUUUGGUUUUGCUUUGUUUUUUGGAUGAAGGAGUGAGGGAAAUGAGGGAAUACCCCCACCAGAAACAGACUGGAAAGCCUGCCUGUCUCUUGGAGAUCCUUCUUUGUCUUGUUAGUGGUACAUGGGAAGUUAUGUUUUUACUGGUGUGUGUGUGUGUGUGUGUGUGUGUACUUAAUGAUGGGAAGGUAAGACUCUGAUCAGGAUUAUGAACUGCGGUCCUUGGGACCAAAGGUGUGGUCAUGGUAGAGAGUUGUAGGACAAUAGGGUGUUUUCAGAAUCUGGGUGGCCACAGAGUGGGAUUUCCUGGUAUGGACAUCAGAAGUCACUGGACUCUUCUCCCAACCCCAGAGUUAUGGGAUUUUGGUGCUUUCUCAGGGUCUCUCCCCAGACUCACUCUUCUCACCCAUAUCCCACAGACUCACUCAUGGAGACCCCCUUGUCAAUAUCCCCUCUACCUUUACUCCUUUGCCCUUUCCCAAUUCAUCUUCUACCACCUGGAUUCUUUUCCAUUCAUGAACUUCAUUCAGCCCUUCCAAAGCCCAAGAUUUGCAUUCCCUUGACAGGGAGGAAAGGCAAUGGUAGGAACCUCUGGUGGUCUGGGUGUCUAUGUGCCUGGUGACCAGGGCUGGAUUUUUAUUACUCUGAGCCCACUGCUAGUGAGGAGCCUUGAGGGGUGGGGACAGGUUGCUGAGUGAUUUUGAACGUUGACACCAGUGUGGAGCCAGUGUGGGUGUGGGGAGCAGUGCCUUCCUCAGGUCCCAGCUGGUCCUGAUAUGCCACGUAGUGGAUGGCAUCUGUCUUGGUCCAUGGGCUUGGUGGGAACAUGCUUCUGCUUGUGUGUUUUCCAUACCUGAGGGCUGACGUAGCUUAAACCACAGGGCAUCAUGCCAAACACUCACUGCUGGGCAGGUUUAUUUCUGGGGAUGUCAGGGUACUGGGGUGUAGGCACUAAGCAGGAUAGAGUUAGGGUGUCUGGCUAGUAAGGGGUUCUGGACGCCUCUGGGGCUGUGAGUUUUCAUCUCAAAGUCUGUUCCAGAGAAAGGAAAGUAGUAUAGAGGUGAUUUUUAGAGAAGCUGAGACCAUGAAAACAAGCCUAAUCCCAUCCAGAAACUGGGGUAAAGUCUGAAAGUUCGUUUUCUUCUUCCUCCCUGAAUAAUUGUUCCAGAAGGGAUGCUAACUCUGCCAGAGCUACAGGCAGAUUUUUGGGCUUUGGAAGUGGAAGCUGAGGCCUGGGGAAGGCUGGGUAAGGAAUGCUGGGGCAAUCUCAGACAGUAGGCAGGUGCUUGGCAUGAAUGAGAAGUGACUUUCCUGGAGUCCCUCAGUAGAGGAUGAGAUAGCAGGGAUUAGGCCACAGUCUCAGAUCCUGAUCUUUUUUCUUCCUAGGAAAGCAUACAUAACUUGUGUCUGCAGAAUCAGUGUGGGAUGAUUUUGCUGGCCCAAGGCUUCAGCGAGAGGGAGAAGAGAGGUCACUACAGCCCUCCUGUGGGUAAAAGCAGCUCUCUUAUAAACCUGCCUCCAUGCAGUGGGGUGGGGGUAAGGGUGGGUGACAGCAAAGAGGUUGAGGAACCUCCCUGGGUUUGGGGAGUGAGAGCUUCCAUGUUCCCUUAAUGUCCUAGGUUAAUUCAUAAGGCAUCUGAGUCCUGGGUCUCACCCAGCCUCACAGAGAGAAAAACUGUCCCUGAGGGUGUCCCCUCCCACUCAAAGGUAGAAAGAGAUUGAGCCAGGAACUGCCCUCAUAUCCUCUGCUCUGCCCCUUCCCUUCCCUUUCCUCUGCCCCUCCCACCUAAAGCUGUUUGGGGCCCUUUCUCAGAGCCCUGGGUGGUGGCAGGCAGGGAGGAGUCCCAAGAUCCUGGUGGCCCUGAGCCCCAUGCUAUGGUUGCCAGAUUUGGCAAAUAAAAAUACAGGAUGUCCAGUUACAUUUGAAUUUCAGUUCAACAACAAACAAUUAUUAAGUGUAAAUAUGUCCUAGGCAAAUAGUUGGGACAUAUACUAAAAAAUAAUUUGUUGUUUAUCUGAAAUUCAAAUGUAACUGGUCAUCCUGCAUUGUGUCUGGGAACCCUACCCUAUGACUUUUCCCCCUCUCCCUUUGGUCCCAAGGGGCCAGGAACCCCAAGGAUUUGACUUAACCAGUUUUUUGAACUGCAAUAUUGAGAAGGGGACACUGUGACUUGAAGACACAUGAAUUACUUUAUUUUUUAAGCAACAACAAAAUAAGAACCUUCUGAAGCCAUUUGAGCCUCAUCUGCCCCCAUCCGUGUAUAUUUAAUUAUAUAUAAAAGAAGAUAAUUACCUAGAAACAUAUGAACAGAAUCUUGUUUAAUCAAGAUGCAUGUCUAUAACUUUCUGUAAAUAGCCGCAUGGCAAUGCUGAGAGUCCCCUUGAUCCCCAACCUCAAACCCAUUUUACAGAACUGGUUGAGGCUGCUCCUUUGAUUUUAUGUCGUGUAAAGUCUUUGUUCCCCAGCCCCACCCCUGCCUCCUCCCAUCGGGAAACCCCCCAUGGGAGUCAUCAGUGGGCGGGAGUCGGUGCCUGCUCCAGUCCAGCCCUGCCUUGGGAGAUGCUGGAGGACCCUGUCGCCCUGAAGGCCUGUUUGCUGCACAUCUGCCUGCAGAGCCAAACCUCAGGGCCCGGUGCAGUGUCCAGCCUGGUAUCUGGCAUCCCAGUAGCUUCCAUGUUCUGUGUAUGUGUGUGGUGUGCCCCUUCCUCCCACUGUUUGAAUUCACUGAAAAGCCAUAAAGGGGGCCUCCUGCUGGAGAUUUGGCCUCCCUUGGCUCCUCCCAGGAGCCCCCAUGUCUCUCCAACUGGCUCCCCACAGACCACUUCUGAAGGGCUCACCUGUUGUCACUCCCUCCUGCUCCCUCAGUCCCGUGUCAUGAGAAUGGACGGUGUCCAGGGCUUCCGGUGGGGUCUCAGGAGAUGCCCAUGCUGGCCCUGCCCGAGCUGGCUUUCUCGGCCUGGGUUCACAGUUCAGCUCCAUCUCUACGCUGGGCGAGGAGCAGACAGCAGUGGGACUCCAUGGUUCUGGAUACCUUUCCUGGGGUCCCUGUGGAGGCAACCAGGAUUUUCAGGAGCAGCCAGUCAGCAGCUCAGCCAGGGAUGACAGAACCAUCCCUGCUUACUCACCUCUGUAGUGUGAGGGUCUGUGGGUGGUGAUGGAGGAGGGACUCAGGGAGAGGCCGGUGAAUACAGGGGCUGACGCUCUUCCCUCGUGCAUCCUCCUGCAGUCUGACAGAAAGCAGCCCAAUAGCGGGGCAACCUCAGGGCUACCAGCGAUCCCCUGAGAGUGGGGUGGGCAGGUUCAGCUGUGAGAGAGGCUCAGGCAGAGCAGGUGUGGACUAAGUCCCCUGACCUUCACACCUGCUCCCCAGAGAAGCCCCAGCCAGUUGCACCAAGUAGCAGAGGUGAGUAGAGGGGCCUGGGGGCUUCCAAGGCCCCAGGUCAUCCUGUUGAACUGAGAGGGACAGGUAGCCCCCCUGCCUGCGGCCCCUGGCCCCAUGGGCACCUGAGGGCAGUACUGCAUGGGAAGAGCCCAGGAUGCCUCAGGCCUGGCAACUGUGACAAGUAUGAGGAAGGAGAGAGAACGGGAAGGGAAUCAGGCAGGGCGCAUUCGAGGAGGCCAGAGGUGGCGAGGCAGGCUUGCCCUGCACAAACCACAACAGAAGUUGCACACAGAAGUCCCAGGGACCUUUGUGCUGGGAACUGAAAGAGUGGGGAAGGUGGAGGGGACCAUUUCAGAGCAGGCUGGAAUCAGGUGCUUGGACCAGUGAAGACAUGUCUUGCUUCCUCCAGCUCUCUCUGGGGCCCUCCCACUCUCCACACCCACAGCAGAGACAAAUUGAGGCAAGAGUUGAGAGAGCAUCUGUCUGGUGAGGUGAUGGGAGCAGUGUGCAUGGGGCACCAGGAGUUCCUCCAUCCCACCUGCCUUAGCGAUCAGGACUUUAGGGGGGCCUCUUCAAAGAUAGUGACCCUUCUGCCCUGACUCCUGCCCAUCUAAGGACUUGAUUUGCUGCUUUCUGAAAACCCUGGGGCUGAAAACUUCAAAAUCAGGGCCUGGCAGAGCCUAGCUUCGCCAAGGUCAGCCCACCAGGAGCCCUGCCUUCGUCUCCAUAGGAAGGACACAUGUACAGCCCUUGCCCCCGGCCCUCUCAUUCCCACUUCUGCUUGGCAAUGCUCUCCAUCUCCCUUAUGUGGACUCUUGUUCUUGUCUGAUCUCUUGUCAAAUUGUUAUUUUGUAAUGAACUGCGUCUCCUUAUUAAAGAAAUGAGCUGAAAGAAA